AUUGCCAAGAUGGCGCCGGUCGCGGUGGCCGCGGAGGCUAGAGUCGGAGAAAGAGGCGGAGGCAGUGGCGGCCGCGAGGGGAGGGGGAGUCCCGUCUGACUGAGACGGCAGGCCUGGGCGGGCGGGCGGGGGUGCCGCGAAGGGCGGAGCGCCGGGCUGGGGAUGAGCUAAGCGGGCUCAGAGCGCCGCGGCAUUCAGCCCCUCGUGUUCCGCUACCGCGCGUGCGGGAUUCCGGCGCCGCUCUCCGAGCUCGAUCCGCUGCUCGCACGGGAGCCAGCUGGGUGUUAUUUCUCAAACUCUGAGGCUGCGGAGUUCACACAUUGAAAUCUGUCAUCUUUUUCAGAGAGAAACUUUCGGUAAUGUGCUUGGGAAAUCCUGAGUUAAGCAAAGUUUAUCGGCUGCCUUUAUCAAAAGACUGCUGAGGAUUUAGUAUUUUUAUAUAUAUAAUGUAACCUUCUGUAAUGGAAGAUGAUUGAAGACAAGGGGCCUCGUGUUGCUGACUACUUUGUUGUAGCAGGAUUAACUGAUGUUUCAAAGCCUCUAGAAGAAGAAAUUCACUUCAAUGAUGCUUGUCAUAAAGUAGCUAAACCAAAAGAACCUAUUACAGAUGUUUCAGUUAUUAUCAAAUCUCUUGGGGAGGAAGUCCCACAGGAUUAUAUCUGUAUUGAUGUUACCCCAACUGGAUUGUCAGCUGAUCUUAAUAAUGGAAGUCUUGUGGGGCCACAGAUUUACCUUUGCUAUAGAAGAGGAAGAGAUAAGCCUCCACUUACAGAUCUGGGGGUUUUAUAUGACUGGAAAGAAAGAUUGAAACAGGGUUGUGAAAUUAUUCAGAGUACUCCCUAUGGGCGCCCCGCAAAUAUUAGUGGGAGUACCUCAUCACAAAGAAUUUAUAUCACUUACCGAAGAGCCUCUGAAAACAUGACUCAGAAUACGUUGGCUGUCACUGACAUAUGUAUUAUUAUACCCAGUAAAGGAGAAAGCCCACCACACACGUUCUGCAAAGUCGACAAGAAUCUCAAUAACAGUAUGUGGGGAUCAGCAGUAUACUUGUGUUAUAAAAAAUCGGUGGCAAAGACGAACACUGUAUCUUACAAAGCUGGCCUAAUUUGUAGAUAUCCUCAAGAAGAUUAUGAGUCAUUCUCACUACCGGAAUCUGUUCCUCUAUUUUGUUUACCAAUGGGUGCAACCAUUGAAUGUUGGCCAUCAAAUAGCAAAUACCCUCUGCCUGUAUUUUCUACUUUUGUUUUAACUGGAGCCUCAGCUGAAAAGGUUUAUGGUGCUGCUAUUCAGUUUUAUGAACCAUACUCUGAGGAGAAUCUCACAGAAAAGCAGAGACUUCUUUUGGGUUUAACAUCAGCAGAUGGGAAGUCUGAUAGUUCCAAAACAAUUCAUACUAACAAAUGCAUCUGUCUUCUUUCUCACUGGCCUUUUUUUGAUGCAUUCAGGAAGUUUCUGACUUUUCUGUAUCGUUAUUCCAUCUCUGGGCCUCAUGUCCUUCCAAUUGAGAAGCAUAUUUCUCAUUUUAUGCAUAAAGUUCCUUUUCCAUCUCCUCAGAGACCACGGAUUUUAGUUCAGUUAUCACCACAUGAUAAUCUGAUUCUCAGUCAGCCUGUGUCUUCACCUCUUCCACUAAGUGGUGGCAAGUUUUCAACACUACUGCAGAAUUUAGGCCCUGAAAAUGCUGUGACACUACUGGUGUUUGCAGUAACAGAACAUAAAAUUCUUAUCCAUUCCCUACGGCCAUCCGUGCUUACUAGUGUGACAGAAGCAUUAGUGUCUAUGAUUUUCCCUUUCCACUGGCCAUGCCCGUAUGUUCCUCUCUGCCCACUGGCUUUAGCAGAUGUCUUGAGUGCACCAUGUCCAUUCAUAGUAGGGAUUGAUUCAAGAUACUUUGAUCUCUAUGAUCCUCCACCAGAUGUCAGUUGUGUUGAUGUAGAUACCAACACUAUUUCUCAAAUUGGUGACAAGAAAAAUGUAGCCUGGAAGAUACUUCCAAAGAAGCCAUGUAAAAAUCUGAUGAACACACUGAAUAAUUUGCAUCAGCAAUUGGCAAAAUUGCAGCAGAGACCGAGAGAUGAUGGACUCAUGGAUUUAGCAAUAAAUGACUAUGAUUUUAAUUCUGGAAAGAGGUUGCACAUGAUAGAUUUGGAAAUCCAAGAGGCAUUUUUGUUUUUCAUGGCCUCUAUUUUAAAAGGUUACAGAUCAUACUUAAGGCCAAUAACACAAGCCCCAUCUGAGACAGCCACAGAUGCAGCCUCUCUCUUUGCCCUACAAGCUUUCUUAAGAAGCCGGGACCGGUCACAUCAAAAAUUCUAUAACAUGAUGACCAAAACACAAAUGUUUAUUCGCUUCAUUGAAGAAUGUUCUUUUGUUAGUGACAAAGAUGCAAGCCUGGCAUUUUUUGAUGAUUGUGUAGAUAAAGUGGAUAUGGACAAGAGCGGUGAAGUACGACUUAUAGAACUGGAUGAAUCUUUCAAAAGUGAACACACUGUUUUUGUAACACCACCUGAGAUCCCCCACCUACCCAAUGGUGAAGAACCCCCUUUACAGUACAGCUAUAAUGGAUUUCCAGUUCUUAGGAACAAUUUAUUUGAAAGACCUGAAGGAUUUCUACAAGCAAAGAAGAACAAAUUGCCUUCAAAAUCAAGUAGUCCUAAUAGCCCUUUGCCCAUGUUCAGAAGAACAAAACAGGAAAUUAAAUCAGCCCAUAAAAUUGCAAAGAGGUACUCUUCCAUCCCUCAGAUGUGGUCUAGGUGUCUACUGCGCCACUGUUAUGGACUGUGGUUUAUUUGUCUCCCAGCUUAUGUGAAAGUCUGUCAUUCAAAAGUCAGGGCUCUGAAAACAGCAUAUGAUGUGCUUAAAAAAAUGCAGUCAAAGAAGAUGGAUCCACCUGAUGAGGUAUGCUACCGCAUUCUUAUGCAACUCUGUGGACAAUAUGAUCAGCCAGUGCUUGCAGUUCGAGUGCUUUUUGAAAUGCAGAAAGCUGGUAUUGACCCCAAUGCCAUUACUUAUGGUUAUUAUAAUAAGGCUGUUUUGGAAAGUACCUGGCCUUCAAGAAGUCGUAGUGGCUAUUUUCUUUGGACAAAAGUAAGAAAUGUUGUUUUAGGAGUAACACAGUUCAAAAGAGCUUUAAAGAAGCAUGCACACUUAUCACAAACAACUCUCUCAGCAGAUGGCAGUGACCUGGAUGCUGUUAGUCAUGGCAGCAUGGAUAGUGGUCAUGGGACACACACUGUGGAGCAGGCACCUUUUAAUACGGGUUUAAUCAAAGUAUAUGCUACUGAUGAUAGAUCUAGUACAGGUGGCCAGUCUGAUCUUGGAUAUAAUUCAUUAUCUAAAGAUGAAGUUAGAAGAGGGGAUACAUCUACUGAAGACAUUCAAGAAGAAAAAGAUAAAAAAGGGAGUGAUUGUAGUUCCUUGUCAGAGAGUGAGAGUACAAAAGGAAGUGCUGAUUGCCUUCCUAAGCUCAGUUAUCAAAAUUCUUCCAGUAUCGUUCGCCUCACUGGUACAAGUAACAACAGUGCUGGUAAAAUAUCAGGAGAAAGCAUGGAAAGCACACCUGAGCUGCUCUUAAUAUCAUCUCUUGAAGAUACAAAUGAAACACGAAACAUUCAAAGUAGAUGCUUCAGGAAAAGACAUAAAAGUGACAAUGAAACUAAUUUGCAGCAGCAAGUGGUCUGGGGAAAUAGAAACCGUAAUCUUAGUGGAGGGGUACUGAUGGGAUUUAUGCUCAAUAGAAUUAACCAGGAAGCAACCCCUGGAGAUAUAGUUGAAAAAUUGGGAGCUGAUGCAAAAAUUCUUUCAAAUGUUAUCUCAAAAAGCACGAGACCAAAUACUCUUGAUAUUGGGAAGCCACCUUUAAGAUCAAAAAGAGACAGUCUAGAAAAGGAAUCUAGUGAUGAUGAUACACCUUUUGAUGGUUCUAACUAUUUGGCAGAUAAAGUGGAUUCUCCUGUUAUUUUUGACUUAGAAGACUUAGACAGUGAAACAGAUGUAUCAAAAGCAGGAUGUGUUGCUACACAAAAUCCCAAGAGGAUUCAACGUAUGAACAGCAGCUUUUCAGUAAAACCUUUUGAAAAAACUGAUGUCGCAACAGGAUUUGAUCCCCUCUCUCUUUUGGUUGCUGAGACUGAACAGCAGCAAAAAGAAGAAGAGGAGGAGGAUGAAGAUGAUAGCAAAAGCAUUUCAACACCAUCUGCUAGGCGUGAUUUAGCUGAAGAAAUUGUGAUGUAUAUGAAUAACAUGAGCAGUCCUUUGACAAGUCGUACACCAAGCAUUGAUUUACAACGGGCAUGUGAUGAUAAAUUAAAUAAGAAAAGUCCACCAUUGGUCAAGGCAUGCAGAAGAUCUAGUCUGCCUCCUAAUUCUCCUAAGCCAGUGAGACUUACCAAAUCUAAAAGUUACACAAAAAGUGAGGAGAAACCAAGGGAUAGACUUUGGUCUUCUCCAGCCUUCUCACCUACUUGCCCAUUUAGGGAAGAAUCUCAGGAUACAUUAACCCACUCAUCACCUUCAUUUAACUUAGAUACACUACUAGUACCUAAACUAGAUGUUCUAAGAAACAGUAUGUUCACUGCUGGAAAAGGAGUUGCAGAGAAAGCAAGCAAAUGGUAUUCAAGAUUCACCAUGUACACCACAUCAUCUAAGGAUCAAAGUUCUGAUCGUACCAGUCUUUCUUCAGUGGGAGCCCAGGAUUCUGAAUCUACCUCUUUAACAGAUGAAGAUGUCUGCCAUGAGUUGGAAGGACCUAUCUCCUCUCAAGAGACCAGUGCUACUUCAGGGACUAAGAGAAUUGAUCUCAGCCGAAUAAGCCUGGAAAGUUCUGCAUCCUUGGAAGGAUCUCUGUCGAAGUUUGCCUUACCUGGGAAAUCAGAAGUGACAUCUUCCUUCAACGCGAGUAAUACAAAUAUCUUCCAGAACUAUGCAAUGGAGGUUCUCAUCUCAAGUUGCUCUCGGUGUAGAACUUGUGAUUGUCUUGUCCAUGAUGAGGAAAUCAUGGCUGGCUGGACAGCAGAUGAUUCAAAUCUCAAUACUACAUGCCCAUUCUGUGGCAAUAUCUUCUUACCCUUUCUGAAUAUAGAAAUAAGAGAUUUAAGACGACCUGGAAGAUACUUUCUAAAGUCAAGCCCAUCAACAGAAAAUAUGCACUUUCCAUCCUCCAUUUCAAGUCAGACGAGGCAGUCUUGCAUUUCAACAUCAGCCUCUGGUCUUGACACAUCUGCUCUCUCUGUUCAAGGGAAUUUUGAUCUAAAUAGCAAAUCUAAACUGCAGGAAAAUUUUUGCACCCGAAGUAUUCAGAUCCCUGCUAAUAGAUCAAAAACAGCUAUGUCUAAAUGUCCAAUAUUUCCAAUGGCCAGGAGUAUUAGUACUUCUGGCCCCUUGGAUAAGGAAGAUACUGGAAGACAGAAGCUCAUUUCUACAGGCAGCCUGCCAGCUACUUUACAAGGAGCUACAGAUUCUUUAGGUUUAGAAUGGCACCUUCCAAGUCCCGAUCCUGUCACUGUUCCGUAUCUUAGUCCUUUAGUGGUAUGGAAAGAACUUGAAAGCUUAUUGGAAAAUGAAGGUGAUCAUGCAAUAACAGUAGCAGACUUUGUGGACCAUCAUCCAAUUGUUUUUUGGAACCUGGUAUGGUAUUUCAGACGUCUUGACUUGCCCAGUAACUUACCUGGAUUGAUUCUUUCUUCUGAGCACUGUAACAAGUAUUCAAAGAUUCCCCGCCACUGUAUGUCUGAAGAUAGCAAAUAUGUUUUAAUACAAAUGUUAUGGGACAAUAUGAAGUUACAUCAGGAUCCGGGACAGCCCUUGUACAUUCUCUGGAAUGCACACAGUCAAAGUCGUACUCUUUUGUUUGAGACCCAAAAAUAUCCAAUGGUCCAUUUAUUGCAAAAAAGUGAUAACUCAUUUAACCAGGAACUGUUGAAAAGUAUGGUAAAAAGCAUUAAAAUGAAUGAUGUCUAUGGACCAAUGAGUCAGAUUUUAGAGACACUGAAUAAGUGUCCACAUUUUAAAAGACAGAGGAGUUUAUACAGAGAAAUACUAUUUCUCUCACUUGUGGCACUGGGAAGAGAAAACAUUGAUAUAGAUGCUUUUGAUAAAGAGUACAAGAUGGCAUACGAUCGUCUCACACCUAGUCAAGUCAAGAGUACACACAACUGUGAUAGACCACCAAGUACAGGGGUGAUGGAAUGUCGAAAAACCUUUGGAGAACCUUAUCUUUAAGAUGUAUUUGUAUGUGUAAACAUUCAAUGUAUAUUGUAUAGUCAGUGUAUAAAAUAACACUUUUAGACUCUAAAUAUUUUUUCUUCAAUUUUUGAAAAUACAAUUUGUAAAUGGUUCAAAAGACUCAGACAGCUUAUGUACAGAAUGUUUGAAGAAGAGAAUAGUGACAAGUGGGGAGAAAGCCACUUUGUUUCUCAUUUCUUUUUUCUUCUUCUUUAACUCCCCUGUAAUAGGAAAUAAAGUAUUUUUGUGAUGAGGAAAUCCCUAAACAAAAUUAGUUGCCAUAAAAUAUGACAACUGCUUUAUGGUUUCUUUUGGAAGAGACAGAUUGAAAAAUCAUGAAUGGAAUCUAAACAGAAAUGUCAGAUGAACGUAUUUCCUGUUUUCAUAGACUAUUCAAAUGUUUUGACCAUGAAGUUGUAUUAUACAUAUUUUAAAUUGUUUAUAGUAAGUUGAUAUUUUUUUAAUUUUUAAAUUUAAUAUAGCAAACUUAAAAUGAAUUUAAACUUAAGCAAGCAAGCGUGUAUUUUCCUUGUCUGCUGCUAUUUGAAGUAAUUAGUACAGCUGCAGAUCUCUCUGUGUAUAUCUAUCUAUAUAUAUAUUUUUUAUUACUUGGGAGAAUGAAUUUUAAAAUGUCAGUGCUAGUGUCAAGUGUUGUCCUAGGAUUGCAUGUUAGUACCCCUAAGCCUGAGUGUGGGGAGUGAGUUAUGCAAGGGUAGCGUGCACUGCCCAGACUGACUCAUGGAGCCUUGUGCAAGGAGAGCCAGAGAGGUUCACUAUACCAUGACUCCAAAAUUGUCUCUAUUGCUAAUAGAUACGUAUAGUAUACAGGGAAAACAGCUUAUAAAUCCAAAUAUCAAUUUAAAUUUUAAUAUUCUACAUGAAAACUUACAUUGGGAAAUAUGCAGACAAGUGAUUAUAUUCCAAAUUUUACCCUUAUUUUAAUAUCUAAAAUAUUGGGUAUGAUGCAAAUUAUACUAUAGAAUAUUUAUCUGAAAUAUGACUUACUGGGGUAUUCUGUUAAUACUAUAUAUAAAUAUUCAGAAUUUUUUUCAAAAGUAGAAAAAUUCCCCUCUAAAAGUACAGCCAGAUAGAUUUUCAUCCAUAUUGAGGAACUUAGCUUUUUCAACAAGCUUCAGAAUCUGAAGUCUGUAGAAUCUAAAAUACAGAAAUAUCCAGAAAUCAGACAAUAAAUUGAAAGUUUAGACAUCAUGAGUAUUAAAUAGCUUUAAAAAUAUAUUUUUAGUCAUAUUAUUUCUAAUGUAACUUUCUUUGGGUAAUUUCUGGUAAGGAAAAACAUCUUUUGGCUGCUAGAAUUAGUUAUAGAUUUUCAAUAUGUGUGUGUGUUUGCACACAUUAUCAUUAGUGAAGGAAUUCCCUAGCCAGCUUUAAAGAAGGAAAAAAUGGAUAGUCCCAAAUUAGGUGUAUAAAGCCAGUAGAGUCCACGACACUUGGACUGGAGGUAUCUUGGAGUCCUGAGACUUAGAAUCAGUUCAGCUGCAGAAAACCCACCUUUUGAGUUCACACCAUUAGUGAAUAGCACCAUGCUGAAACAUUUCACAGCUUCCAACUCUGGGAAAUAAUGGAGAGAGUUUAAAAAUGUAAAACUUCAGUUAGUUUGGGGCUGAACUUGCUUACUUGAAAAAUCUGGUGCUAGGCACAUAUAUCUGCCUCUCCUUUGUAAAUACCACUCCAAUAUUAUUCUUUACUAUUCAGAUCCAAGCUUCAUGUUCUACUUGUUCUUCAUGUUCUUUAAAUCAUUUGAAAGUUGUCAACUGAGAGAAACAUUUCAGAGGGGGGAGGCUUUUGGCACUGGUGAUAAACAUCCCUCCAAGAGAACCGUCUGGGGUUCUCUUCUAUUUGUGGUUGGUGGUUUUUAUUCUUUUAAAAACAGCUUUCAUUGUUGUUUACUUUUUGUGUAAUACAAACAAAAUGUAGGAAUCAUAGUUUAUUGAUUUCAAAUGGCUGACAAAGAAUGAGUAAAACCAUUCUUUAUGGUUUUACGAUUCAGACUCAUUUGGAAAAGCGAAUGUAAUUUUUACCUCCUCUUUCCACCCCAAGUUUUGUUUCUGCUUUUGGAGAGGGUUGUAUUUCCCCUACUUUUAAUCCCUAGGGAAUAUUAUUGCACAGAUUUAGUCUUAAAACCUAAAACACAAAUACAAAGUGGUAAACCUGUUCAAAAGAAAAUUAAAAUGUGAAUCAUUCUUGAGCUGGGCGUGGUUGCUCAUGGAGGCCUGUAAUCCCAGCACUUUGGGAGGCUGAAGCAGGGAGGAUUGCUUGAGUCCAGGAGUUCAAAACCAGCCUGAGCAACAUAGAGAGACCCUGUCUCUACAAAAAAAUUUUUUAAAUUUGCUCGGUAUGGUGGCUCAUGCUUGGUAAUCCCAGCUACUCGGGAGGCUGAAGCAGGAGGAUCACUUUGAGCCUGGGGGUUUGGGGCUGCAAUGAGCUGUGAUCAUGCCAUUGCACUCUAGCCUGGAUUACAGAGCAAGACCCUGUCUCAAAAAAAAAAAAAAAAAAAAAAAAAAAAACCAGAAAAUAUCAAUCAUUUAAAAUAACUCUAUACAAACUUUUCUUCAAUUUUCUGUUAACCAUACAUUUUGGAGAAUAAUGGCCAAUCAUGUUGGAGAGAAAUGCCCUUUUGCUACAGCAUCUGUCUUUUAUUUUCUUACUCUUAGUUUUGUUUAUAUGUUUAAAUGGUUGACAAUAAACCAUGUCCUGUGCUGAUGUA